CUCUAGUCAUCGCCCUCGCAGCGGCGGCCAACAUCACCGCCACUGCCACCCCUCCCAGACUGUGGACGGGAGGAUGGAGUCGAUGGCCGUCGCUACCGACGGCGGGGAGAGGCCGGGGGUCCCAGCGGGCUCAGGUCUGUCGGCUUCCCAGCGUCGGGCGGAGCUGCGUCGGAGAAAGCUGCUCAUGAACUCGGAACAGCGCAUCAACCGGAUCAUGGGCUUUCACAGGCCCGGGAGCGGCGCGGAAGAAGAAAGUCAAACAAAAUCAAAGCAGCAGGACAGUGAUAAACUGAACUCCCUCAGCGUUCCUUCCGUUUCAAAGCGAGUAGUGCUGGGUGAUUCAGUCAGUACAGGAACAACUGACCAGCAGGGUGGUGUGGCCGAGGUAAAGGGGACCCAACUGGGAGACAAAUUGGACUCGUUCAUUAAACCACCUGAGUGCAGUAGUGAUGUCAACCUUGAGCUCCGGCAGCGGAACAGAGGGGACCUGACAGCGGACUCGGUCCAGAGGGGUUCCCGCCAUGGCCUAGAGCAGUACCUUUCCAGAUUCGAAGAAGCAAUGAAGCUAAGGAAACAGCUGAUUAGUGAAAAACCCAGUCAAGAGGAUGGAAAUACAACAGAAGAAUUUGACUCUUUUCGAAUAUUUAGAUUGGUGGGAUGUGCUCUUCUUGCUCUUGGAGUCAGAGCUUUUGUUUGCAAAUACUUGUCCAUAUUUGCUCCAUUUCUUACUUUACAACUUGCGUACAUGGGAUUAUACAAAUAUUUUCCCAAGAGUGAAAAGAAGAUAAAGACAACAGUACUAACAGCUGCACUUCUAUUGUCGGGAAUUCCUGCCGAAGUGAUAAAUCGAUCAAUGGAUACCUAUAGCAAAAUGGGCGAAGUCUUCACAGAUCUCUGUGUCUACUUUUUCACUUUUAUCUUUUGUCAUGAACUGCUUGAUUAUUGGGGCUCUGAAGUACCAUGAAGCCUGUAGAACUGAGAAGGAGAAGCUUACAAAAAAAAAAAAAUCCUCUUCUAUAUUGCAGUGUCUCUAAAGGAGGCAAAUUGGUUUACACCUUCAUGUAAUUCUUUUACUUUAGGGGUUGUAAAGCUACUUUAUUAGAUAUAGAAUGGCAGAUUCUCUGAUUUAAAAGGGCUGAGUUUGUAUUAUUACUGAUAUGAAGAAUAGAGUACCAAUGUCAUUAAUUGAUUUUUCUUGUUAAUCAGAAUUCCUAUUCUGUACCUUUCCUCUAACUUCUCAGAUUUGUAAUUCUUCUUUUGGGAGCUGAGCUAGUGCUUUUAGGAGAACAGAUAAAUGUGGUCUCAGCCAGCCCUAGAGACUGCUUCUUGUGUUUGUGUCAUUCUGUCCUGAGAAAUGAAGUCAUCUGAAAAAUAAAAUGAAAGAAACUGAAUUGUCUAAUGUUAACUCUGCACAUUGUAACUUUUCUUGUUGAGUUAGUAUCUUAAUUUUUACUCCAGCACAAGUAUUUAAUCAAAGAAAAGAUUCAUACAUGUGAAAUUGGAAGGUAUUUAUAAAAUUUUUAUUGCUGUAUACCAAACUCAGAAUUGGAACUUUUUACAUUUGAGUUUCACUUUUUAGAAGUAUGUUUUAAGCAAGCAAAAACAAAAUGGGAUGUGAAGAAUUGAGGCAUGCAACCCAAUAGCAUAAAUGUCCUUUUUCCCCCCAAAUAUGGUCUAGAUGAGUUAUUAUAAACAUUGUUUUUAUUUUUUUGAGACAGAGUUUCGCUCUUGUUGCCCAGGCUAGAGUGCAAUGGCGCCAUCUCGGCUCACCGCAACCUCCACCUUCCUGGUUCAAGGGAUUCUCCUGCCUCAGCCUCCCAAGUAGCUGGGAUUACAGGCAUGCACCACCACGCCCAGCUAAUUUUUAUAUUCUUUAGUAAAGACAGGGUUUCUCCAUGUUGGUCAGGCUGGUCUCGAACUUCUGACCUCAGGUGAUCUGCCCACCUCGGCCUCCCAAAGUGCUGGGAUUACAGGCGUGAGCCACUGCACCUGGCCUUAUAAAUAUCCUUUUAACUAACUCAGUAACUGCCAUAUUUUGUUGGGUUGUCUUCUUAAAAGAAUAUAAGACUAAAGUGUUAAUGUCACUUGGUGUUACAUUUCCUUACAGAUUUUUGUAUAGUCUAAUUUGGUUAAUCCUUGUGACAUUAAAAACACAUACACUUUUUAAAAAA